GCAGUCCUGCGGGGCGCCGGCGGCGAUGGGUUGGGGAAAUGGACGCCUGGAGAACGGAAAUCCAGUUAUCAAAAUGGACUCGGGAAGAGAGAACCUAACAGAACAAUAACAAUGGAAGAAAUUGGGAACAUUAUCACAAAGCUAUCAUCCUGCCAAACUCCAGGCUCAGAUGAUGUCACAGGUUAAAAAAUGCCCUUCAUGAGAAAGAUCUUAAGCAACAUGAUAGAUUCAGAAGCUCAUGAAAAGAGGCCACCAAUACUUACAUCUUCAAAACAAGAUAUAUCACCUCAUAUUACAAAUGUUGGUGAAAUGAAGCAUUACUUGUGUGGCUGCUGUGCAGCCUUCAACAACGUCGCAAUCACAUAUCCCAUUCAGAAGGUCCUCUUUCGGCAACAGCUGUAUGGCAUCAAAACCCGGGAUGCAGUACUUCAGUUGAGAAGGGAUGGAUUUCGAAAUUUGUAUCGUGGAAUCCUUCCCCCAUUGAUGCAGAAGACAACUACGCUUGCACUUAUGUUUGGUCUGUAUGAGGAUUUAUCCUGCCUUCUCCGGAAGCAUGUCCGUGCUCCAGAGUUUGCAACCCAUGGCGUGGCGGCAGUGCUUGCAGGGACAGCAGAAGCAAUUUUCACUCCACUGGAAAGAGUUCAGACAUUGCUUCAAAACCACAAGCAUCAUGACAAAUUUACCAACACUUAUCAGGCUUUCAAGGCACUGAAAUGUCAUGGAAUUGGAGAGUAUUAUCGAGGCUUGGUGCCCAUUCUUUUCCGGAAUGGACUCAGCAAUGUCUUGUUUUUCGGCCUUCGAGGUCCCAUUAAGGAGCAUCUGCCUACCGCAACGACUCACAGUGCUCAUUUGGUCAAUGAUUUUAUCGGUGGAGGUCUAUUGGGUGCCAUGUUGGGAUUCUUGUGUUUUCCAAUUAAUGUUGUAAAAACUCGCCUACAGUCUCAGAUUGGUGGGGAAUUUCAGUCUUUCCCCAAGGUUUUCCAAAAAAUCUGGCUGGAACGGGACAGAAAACUGAUAAAUCUUUUCAGAGGUGCCCAUCUGAAUUACCAUCGGUCCCUCAUCUCUUGGGGCAUAAUCAAUGCAACUUAUGAGUUCUUGUUAAAAUUUAUAUGAAAAAAAACCAUCAGUUAAGUGCCAUUUAUCAACUGAAUAGACCUUCUAAGAAGAAUGCAGUUUGGCCUCUUUCUUAAUUGGCCAAAUACAAGUUCGUGUCAUAACUCCAGGCCACAGUGAGUUACGGGCAAAGCUGUUUUCCUUAAGCAUCAACAAAACAGAAUAAAAGGUUCCAAUAGGAAAA